AUAAAAAUACCUUCAGUCAUUCCCAGUGCCUGGCCCAUACAGAGGCACAGCUCCCAGUGUAUUGACACUCCAUGGGAUCUUCUCACCAUCAGCAUGACCUUGACCUAUCUAAGAAUGAUGCCAAGUAGAAAAUGGGUUGCCUCUCUGGGUGUGUGUCUGCAGGAAGAGCAGACUGUUUCCCACUGUUGAGUAAGUUCCUCCAGGCCAGUCCUGUCUGCAGACACUUGUACCAGCUCUUUCCCGAGGUGCACUCACACCUUCUUCCCUUCGGGUGAGGGGCUCAAAUGACCCUCUUACUGGUGAGGUUUCCUGGUGAGGUCCACUGUCCCUAAAAGUUCAAUACACACCCUCUUCCCUUGCUCUUUUAUUUUUUUCUCCUUAAUUCUACUCUUUCUAACUCAUUCUGUUCCCUUAGCUUGCCUAUUAUCUGUUGGCCCCACUGAAUGCAAGCUCCAUGAGGGCUGAGAUUUUUUUGUUCUCUUCAUUCCCAUAUCCCCAAAGCCUAGAACAAUGCCUGGCACCUAGUCGGUGUUGAAUAAAUACUUGGGGAAUAAUGGAAUGAUGUGUGAUAGGCUGUUCUGAUUUUCUUCCUCUAAAGCCUGACUUCCUCUAACUGCCCAAAUAGGGUUCAUAAAUAUCCUAUCAGAGUGAAUAGUCACCUGCCUCCUUGCUGAGAAAUCAUGAAAGGAUGGGAUGAGUAAUGACAUCCUACAGGUAGAAAAUACUUCUCAGCCUCAUCACCAUUCGUCAUCAAAAGUAAGUUCUUGAACAAUAAACGAGGCAUUUUUUUCUUCAUUACAUAGAGGAAAUGGUAGCGAUAUUGGCUGACCCAGUCCGAGGAAAUGGCAGGAAUGUUUGUGGAAGGGCUGCUGGACUCCCCAUUGACCUUGCUGGGUCGCCUGAGCAAGUCAGAAAAACCCCAGGUUGGUGGGAAGAGAAGCCACUCACACCUGCUCAUGGCUGGAGCUGUCACCCAUGGUCAGGAGUUGCUGGAAGUUUGAAUUGUCCUGACCUGGAAGGCAGGCGGCAUGCUGGUGAGCUCAGGCCAUGUGGAAAGGAGCCCUGAGAAAGGAUCUGUUCAGUGUUGGUGAAUUCAUCAAGACCUCAUUUCGCAUCUGAGGAGGACAUCGCUACUUUCCUUUUAAAACAGAGGCAUCCCUGAAGAAUUAAUGCUAGGAUGCUGUUCCUCAGAGCAAGGUUGAAAACCCGUGAAUUGGAUGACGACCAUUUAUGUAUGCAUGAUUCUAAAUGAGAAAGAAUUUUGUUAACACUUGGGAGUUGUCCUUCAGCAGAAUGAGGAAAAGCUAAGGGAAGUAGAAAUAGAUUAUUACACAGAUCACUAUACAGUCUGACAACACCCAAUGCAGACACAAAAAUACAAUGAUGAUCUUUGCCAAUGAUGAUCUGUUCUGUUCUCCUCUCCUACACAUUCUGAAGUUUAAAUCCUGGACUUAAACUGUUCUCCUUCAUCCUAUUUGGAUGGGAAACCCCCAAAAAACCCAAUGUUUGUGUGUUUGUUGCUUUGAAAGGAAUGAGAUGGGGAAGGCAUGUCUGAGCUUAGUGAACGGAGCUGGUCUCAGCUCUCCAAUCCCUGGGGUCUACGGACGUUCUCUGCUCCUUUGGGAAACAGGCCAAUUCAGACCACUCUUUUCCAGGCUUCUCUUAAUUGCUGUGAUUCUGGCUAUAAACCCUUCCUGAGACUUAACAUUUAUCCUAGAGUCUUUCCUAAUUAACUCUAAUAUUUUCUAGAAAUCACUUCCCUUCUAGAAUGAACUGAUAAUGGUUUGUCACAGAACUAAGUUGCGUAUCACUGAGUGAGAAUGAUGUUUCAUCUCCUAGAUCAGGCCUGGAGACAUAUAUGUCCUAGGAAAACUCUCAGAUACAGAAGAAGUUUCCAUCUGUACCUCCAUGAAAUUGAUUUUUAUUUCUUUCUUUCUUUCUUUUUGCAAAGAGAAGAACUGCUCUUAAGUCCCUGUGUAAUAUACCAAUUACUUCAAUAUAAUACCCUUCUAAAUUGCAAAAACAUUAUCAUUUUUCUUGUGAAUCAUUGUUUGAACCUAGUUAGUAUAUUUUGAUACCAGGAAUAACCAGUCUGUCUGCCAGGGGAAGUUACAAAGAUUUCAAGAUUGUUACAGCACUAUGAGUAAGUCCUGGUAUGUUGCCUUUGCAUCCACAGAGGAGCACUUUCAUUUAUUAAUUUAUUUGUAAAUUAGAAUUAUUAAUAUACUCCAGAGUUAAUAGCCCGAGGUUGAUAGAAACCACUUGGAGGGAAAACUAAUGCAGGAACAGAAAACCAAAUACUGCAUGUUCUCAUUUAUAAGUGGGAGCUAACAUUGAGUACAUAUGGAUGCAAAGAAGGGAACAACAGACACUGGGAAAGGAGAGGAUCAAAAGACUCCCUGUGGAGAACUGUGCUUAUUGCCUGGGUGAUGAAAUAAUCUGUACACCAAACCUCGCUAACAUGCAGUCUACCUACAUAACAAACCUGCCCAUGUACCCCUGAACCUACAAUUAAAGUUAAAAAAAAAAAGUUAAGGGCCAGGCUUAAAGGCUCAUGCCUAUAAUCCCAGCACUUUGGGAGGCCGAGGCGGGCAGAUCACCUGAGCUCAGGAGUUUGAGGCCAGCCUGGCCAACAUGGUGAAACCCCAUCUCUACUAAAAAUACAAAAUUAGCCAGGCAUGGUGGUGGGCGCCUGUAAUCCCAGCUACUUGAGAGGCUGAGGCAGGAGAGUUACUUGAAUCCGGGAGGCGGAGGUUGCAGUGAGACACUGCACUCCAGCAUGGGCAACAGAGUGAGACUCGGUCUCAGAAAAUGAAGUUAAGAAAAAAUAAAUACCUGGUCAUUAAAAAUCUGUGCCUAAUAGUAUGCCUUAUAUACUUGGGGAAGAAAAGGGAAACCACUCGGAGAGGAUGGUGCAGUGUUAUCAGUUUGGUCCUGGAAAUCAGCAUGAUCUCAAAAUUCACCAAGCUCAAUCAUUAAGUGGCCGCUGGUCUACCAUCAUCAGGGGAGCGUAGCAGCUUGCGUUGGUUUGGCCAAUUGAUUGAGAUCCAGUUCUAAUGUCAUCCUUAUAAAUGUCUCCAUUGGGAGAGGGUGCUUGGGUUUGCUGGACAGCAGCCCCUGCUCCCUCUCUAAGUAAUAAAACUUUCUGGGUUUCUGGCAUGCUUAUACCUUAAUAAUCCUUGCUGCCUCAAGACAUGGGAAAAUGCAUUUGUAAAAAGUGAGACACUCUGUGUAUGUUGGAUAACACUGGCUGCUUUGGAAUCAAACCCCAAAUGCUCAGUGGGUUACCAUAUUAGAAGCGUGUUUUCCUUCUGUAUGAUGCUCUGAGGCUCUAGGCUGCAGGUGGCCUUCCUCCAUACAGUGAGUUAGGACCAGAUGCCAUGCCUGACACCUCCAUCUCCUAAAACCGUGGGAUACUCUAAUCUCAGCUGGCAGAUGGGGAAAGAAAGGAUAUGAAGAAGGAAUACUCGCUUAAAUACCAUCAGCCAAAAGUGACCUAUAUCACUUUUGUUCAUGUUCUAGUGCCAAGAAUGUCAUACAGCCCACCCAGGUACAUGGGGGCUGGGCAGCCCUUCUAGAGCACAGAAGGGGAGCAUAACUUUGCUGGGGAGUUGGCUGACCCUGCCACACCCGGUUGUUUAGAGGCACCCGGUUGUUUAGACCCUGCCACACCGUGGAAUUUAGAGACAAGGGUACCCAUUUCCCAUGGUGUUCAGCAGUUGCAGCAGGAAGGACUUGGAGACCAGCCUGGAGAAAGGAAUGGGGGUGUGCCUGUUUAACCUGCCGGAAGUCAGGGAGUCUUUCGGGGGCCAGAAGUGUGGGAACAGAUUUGUGGAAGAAGGAGAGGAGUGUGACUGUGGGGAGCCAGAGGAAUGUAUGAAUCGCUGCUGCAAUGCCACCACCUGUACCCUGAAGCCGGACGCUGUGUGCGCACAUGGGCUGUGCUGUGAAGACUGCCAGCUGAAGCCUGCAGGAACAGCGUGCAGGGACUCCAGCAACUCCUGUGACCUCCCAGAGUUCUGCACAGGGGCCAGCCCUCACUGCCCAGCCAACGUGUACCUGCACGAUGGGCACUCAUGUCAGGAUGUGGACGGCUACUGCUACAAUGGCAUCUGCCAGACUCACGAGCAGCAGUGUGUCACGCUCUGGGGACCAGGUGCUAAACCUGCCCCUGGGAUCUGCUUUGAGAGAGUCAAUUCUGCAGGUGAUCCUUAUGGCAACUGUGGCAAAGUCUCGAAGAGUUCCUUUGCCAAAUGCGAGAUGAGAGAUGCUAAAUGUGGAAAAAUCCAGUGUCAAGGAGGUGCCAGCCGGCCAGUCAUUGGUACCAAUGCCGUUUCCAUAGAAACAAACAUCCCCCUGCAGCAAGGAGGCCGGAUUCUGUGCCGGGGGACCCACGUGUACUUGGGCGAUGACAUGCCGGACCCAGGGCUUGUGCUUGCAGGCACAAAGUGUGCAGAUGGAAAAAUCUGCCUGAAUCGUCAAUGUCAAAAUAUUAGUGUCUUUGGGGUUCACGAGUGUGCAAUGCAGUGCCACGGCAGAGGGGUGUGCAACAACAGGAAGAACUGCCACUGCGAGGCCCACUGGGCACCUCCCUUCUGUGACAAGUUUGGCUUUGGAGGAAGCACAGACAGCGGCCCCAUCCGGCAAGCAGAUAACCAAGGUUUAACCAUAGGAAUUCUGGUGACCAUCCUGUGUCUUCUUGCUGCCGGAUUUGUGGUUUAUCUCAAAAGGAAGACCUUGAUACGACUGCUGUUUACAAAUAAGAAGACCACCAUUGAAAAACUAAGGUGUGUGCGCCCUUCCCGGCCACCCCGUGGCUUCCAACCCUGUCAGGCUCACCUCGGCCACCUUGGAAAAGGCCUGAUGAGGAAGCCGCCAGAUUCCUACCCACCGAAGGACAAUCCCAGGAGAUUGCUGCAGUGUCAGAAUGUUGACAUCAGCAGACCCCUCAACGGCCUGAAUGUCCCUCAGCCCCAGUCAACUCAGCGAGUGCUUCCUCCCCUCCACCGGGCUCCACGUGCACCUAGCGUCCCUGCCAGACCCCUGCCAGCCAAGCCUGCACUUAGGCAGGCCCAGGGGACCUGUAAGCCAAACCCCCCUCAGAAGCCUCUGCCUGCAGAUCCUCUGGCCAGAACAACUCGGCUCACUCAUGCCUUGGCCAGGACCCCAGGACAAUGGGAGACUGGGCUCCGCCUGGCACCCCUCAGACCUGCUCCACAAUAUCCACACCAAGUGCCCAGAUCCACCCACACCGCCUAUAUUAAGUGAGAAGCCGACACCUUUUUUCAACAGUGAAGACAGAAGUUUGCACUAUCUUUCAGCUCCAGUUGGAGUUUUUUGUACCAACUUUUAGGAUUUUUUUUAAUGUUUAAAACAUCAUUACUAUAAGAACUUUGAGCUACUGCCGUCAGUGCUGUGCUGUGCUAUGGUGCUCUGUCUACUUGCUCAGGUACUUGUAAAUUAUUAAUUUAUGCAGAAUGUUGAUUACAGUGCAGUGCGCUGUAGUAGGCAUUUUUACCAUCACUGAGUUUUCCAUGGCAGGAAGGCUUGUUGUGCUUUUAGUAUUUUAGUGAACUUGAAAUAUCCUGCUUGAUGGGAUUCUGGACAGGAUGUGUUUGCUUUCUGAUCAAGGCCUUAUUGGAAAGCAGUCCCCCAACUACCCCCAGCUGUGCUUAUGGUACCAGAUGCAGCUCAAGAGAUCCCAAGUAGAAUCUCAGUUGAUUUUCUGGAUUCCCCAUCUCAGGCCAGAGCCAAGGGGCUUCAGGUCCAGGCUGUGUUUGGCUUUCAGGGAGGCCCUGUGCCCCUUGACAACUGGCAGGCAGGCUCCCAGGGACACCUGGGAGAAAUCUGGCUUCUGGCCAGGAAGCUUUGGUGAGAACCUGGGUUGCAGACAGGAAUCUUAAGGUGUAGCCACACCAGGAUAGAGACUGGAACACUAGACAAGCCAGAACUUGACCCUGAGCUGACCAGCCGUGAGCAUGUUUGGAAGGGGUCUGUAGUGUCACUCAAGGCGGUGCUUGAUAGAAAUGCCAAGCACUUCUUUUUCUCGCUGUCCUUUCUAGAGCACUGCCACCAGUAGGUUAUUUAGCUUGGGAAAGGUGGUGUUUCUGUAAGAAACCUACUGCCCAGGCACUGCAAACCGCCACCUCCCUAUACUGCUUGGAGCUGAGCAAAUCACCACAAACUGUAAUACAAUGAUCCUGUAUUCAGACAGAUGAGGCUUUCCAUGGGACCACAACUAUUUUCAGAUGUGAACCAUUAACCAGAUCUAGUCAAUCAAGUCUGUUUACUGCAAGGUUCAACUUAUUAACAAUUAGGCAGACUCUUUAUGCUUGCAAAAACUACAACCAAUGGAAUGUGAUGUUCAUGGGUAUAGUUCAUGUCUGCUAUCAUUAUUCGUAGAUAUUGGACAAAGAACCUUCUCUAUGGGGCAUCCUCUUUUUCCAACUUGGCUGCAGGAAUCUUUAAAAGAUGCUUUUAACAGAGUCUGAACCUAUUUCUUAAACACUUGCAACCUACCUGUUGAGCAUCACAGAAUGUGAUAAGGAAAUCAACUUGCUUAUCAACUUCCUAAAUAUUAUGAGAUGCUGGCUUGGGCAGCAUCCCCUUGAACUCUUCACUCUUCAAAUGCCUGACUAGGGAGCCAUGUUUCACAAGGUCUUUAAAGUGACUAAUGGCAUGAGAAAUACAAAAAUACUCAGAUAAGGUAAAAUGCCAUGAUGCCUCUGUCUUCUGGACUGGUUUUCACAUUAGAAGACAAUUGACAACAGUUACAUAAUUCACUCUGAGUGUUUUAUGAGAAAGCCUUCUUUUGGGGGUCAACAGUUUUCCUAUGCUUUGAAACAGAAAAAUAUGUACCAAGAAUCUUGGUUUGCCUUCCAGAAAACAAAACUGCAUUUCACUUUCCCGGUGUUCCCCACUGUAUCUAGGCAACAUAGUAUUCAUGACUAUGGAUAAACUAAACACGUGACACAAACACACACAAAAGGGAACCCAGCUCUAAUACAUUCCAACUCGUAUAGCAUGCAUCUGUUUAUUCUAUAGUUAUUAAGUUCUUUAAAAUGUAAAGCCAUGCUGGAAAAUAAUACUGCUGAGAUACAUACAGAAUUACUGUAACUGAUUACACUUGGUAAUUGUACUAAAGCCAAACAUAUAUAUACUAUUAAAAAGGUUUACAGAAUUUUAUGGUGCAUUACGUGGGCAUUGUCUUUUUAGAUGCCCAAAUCCUUAGAUCUGGCAUGUUAGCCCUUCCUCCAAUUAUAAGAGGAUAUGAACUGAGUUUUUCUUUUGUUGUUUGUUCUUAGCUGUAAUUCCUAUGCUUCUAUUUCAGAGAGCCAGGAGAGUUUGAUAUUAAAGGAGGUUAAAACUGUGAUCUUAUGCCAUGUCAUCAAUGGCCACUUAGGGGCCAUGGCUGAUGACACAUUCUUAUCUCUACAGUACUAAUGUGUUAUUAUAGAGCCAUGCAUUUUAUUUCUGAAUAAGAACAUAUUUAAACUAAUAUUCCCUUACAAUAUGGACAGUAUUAAUCCUUCCAAGAUGCAGUAUUUAUCAAGUGAAGCAUAUUUAGCAGCAAAUUCCAUUUUAACAUAACUUAGGAACCAAUAACCAGGGUGUUUUGUGGUUGGGGGAGGCACGGGGUGGAGUAUUCUUUUUUAUAUCCUCAAAACAAAAAAAAUCAAUACUUAUAUUUCAAUGGCAAUCUAGUAUUUUUUUAAAAGACUGUAUAGGCAUGAAUAAUAGAGGUGGUUUGAGUUUUGUAGGGCCAUCACCUGGAAAGUCAAUGUGACUAGACACAAAGUAGCCCAGAGGCUACUUUUCUUCCUACAGCUUAUUAUAGUUGUAGGUUCUAUGACCUCACUUCAUGGGUUCCAGGCAAUUCCGCUGAAAGGUUUGUCUCCUGAAAUUUUUUAAGUUUGUUUUCCUGACACAUGUAAUCAGAUGUGUAGCAACCGAGGGAAACGAAGCCUAACAUUCUCCAUUGUGGAAAUACACACAGGAGGUUACAUUUCACAGCGUGGAUUUUUCCAGCUUACACAUGUGGGAUGACAUCACAGAAACCACAAAAGCAGCAAAUUAAACUGUAGGAGAGUCAAUACUCCUGACGAGUCUCGGGGGGGGGGCAUUUUUAUGCCUUCUUAACUUUAUGAGAAUUCUCAGGCUGAACUAUAGGCCAUUGUUCCCAGGCAAAUCAAUACAUCAAUGCAUCCUCAAAAAAAAAAAAAAAAAAAAAAAACCGGCUAAAACUGUGUCAAAAUGUUCUUAAGGAGCCUAUGGUCUCCACGGUGCUAAAAAGAGCCUGGUGCUGGGCCGACUGGCAGGGCUGAGCAUCCUCCUGCCCCCUCGCCACUGAUGUUUACUAAGCACUCUGAGCCAAUGAGACCCCCAGCAGCAGAAAGGGCACAAGGUGGCGCCAGGGCAGCAGGGCCAGAUCUUUCUCAUGCACCUCGACCUCUUGCAGACUUUCUUCGUGAGAUGUACUACUCAUUUCAAAACUGCUUUGCAGGGCUCCCCUAUGUAUUCGGGGGGCCCACGGCACACUCAGGCUGGAGAUCCUUCCUCACUGCGCUCAAGAUGGCCUCAGCCAGACACCAGUUACCCAGCUGAAAGUCACAAUCCCUCCCAGAAGUCUCCCAACACUAGUGCUGACCAGAGGUGGGGCUCUCAGGCUAGGAGUUUCACACACAAUGACAGGCUGCUGGGGGACAUUGCAGGACCCCUUUUCCUCUCCUCUCCAUGCUAGAAGCCAGCCCUAGGCAGCUGCAGUUACUCCCUGUGACUCAGCAGCAGGCUGAUUCAACACAGCUGCCCACACAAAGCCAGUGGCUAAUACAUCUGUUUACCUUUCCCUAUCACCCAGACACAAGCCCCUUUCCCAGGUCAAACCACAGGCCGAUGCAUCUCCAGUUUGACAGUCAAAUCACUACUUCCAUUGCUACUUUAGAUCAGCCAAAGUGGUGACUGCUGCAGUGUGUGGCUAUCCCUACAAGGCCCACCCAAGGGAUGCCCAAAGCCCAACCUUCUCCAGGGCUGCAGCCCAGAGCAACCCCACCAGCCUAAGUCCAGCAGAGGACCUCCCACCCAAUGUCUUGUUCUAAUUAGAAGGGGAAGUUAGCCACAGAAAAUCAACUUAUCUAUAAUUACAAAAUUCUCUUGACUCACCUUAAAGUUCCUAUUGACAUCUACUGCUUUUAAACCUAUUUGAAAACUCUGAUACUAAAACAAAUGACACUCUAAGAAAGUUUGGGAGCCCCAUGCUGAGAACCAUUUCUGUGCAGUGAGGAUGUUUCCAGAAGCUACUUACCUACAUGUGAAUGUGCCAUUUUCUUUCCUUUUGUAGAGAAAAUCCCCUUUACUUUUUGGAACAGUAAUGGCAGCUUCUAGUACAGCCAUUACAGUUUCAUAUGAGAAAAAUUAAGAAUAACUAUAAAAUUGUUAAAAUAUCCAAUAAUGGAUAAUGAUGGCCAGAAGAUUUAACAUACAAAGUAAUUCUCAAUGUAAAGCUAUUCAGCUCUUCCAGGUUGAAUGCCCUGUAACCCACCCUGACCUUCCACAUCAUCUUCAAAAAGCAGUUUCUCUGUUCCCCAUGAUUCUCCUAUAAGGUAACUCUUUAGUCCUCCAUUUAGCACAUUUUAAAUCCUCCAAAGAAUAAGUAUCAUGUGAUUAUUUUAGCUUUACAAAAAAAAAGUUGAAUGGCGUUUUAUUUUCAUGGCCUAUAAGCAGGUACCUUAGUAGGGCAGAUAUAGGAAAAACAAAUUAGAGCAAAACAAAUCCUCUACAAAUCCAAGGCAGGAAAAGUGGUGGCAGAGUGACUCAUUCUCCUGUCCCUCCCAUCAGGUCAAAUCAGGAGGCUGCAGUGAAUGCCUGUUCUUUGAAUGUGUAGCAGUUGUUCCUGUAACUCUUUAAAACUUGGCUAUAGGCUGUUUAGCACAGUACAGAUUAAAGAUACAGUUACGUAAACAGCAAAGUAAUUUUAUAGUGCUUCAUCCAUUUAUCAUGCUUUGGUUUGCUAAUUUUUUCACAUACCUUUUUCUAUCACAGUCUGUUGCUUUUGUACACAUUUCUCAUAUUGGGGUUCGACAGGUAAACACAAACUGCUAUUUCAGUAGAAAAAGUUAUUGUUAUGAAUAUUAAACCCAAUAAAUUGUAUAAAGGUAAA